CUUCCUGACCGGCGCGCGCAGCCUGCUGCCGCGGUCAGCGCCUGCUCCUGCUCCUCCGCUCCUCCUGCGCGGGGUGCUGAAACAGCCCGGGGAAGUAGAGCCGCCUCCGGGGAGCCCAACCAGCCGAACGCCGCCGGCGUCAGCAGCCUUGCGCGGCCACAGCAUGACCGCUCGCGGCCUGGCCCUUGGCCUCCUCCUGCUGCUACUGUGUCCAGCGCAGGUGUUUUCACAGUCCUGUGUUUGGUAUGGAGAGUGUGGAAUUGCAUAUGGGGACAAGAGGUACAAUUGCGAAUAUUCUGGCCCACCAAAACCAUUGCCAAAGGAUGGAUAUGACUUAGUGCAGGAACUCUGUCCAGGAUUCUUCUUUGGCAAUGUCAGUCUCUGUUGUGAUGUUCGGCAGCUUCAGACACUAAAAGACAACCUGCAGCUGCCUCUACAGUUUCUGUCCAGAUGUCCAUCCUGUUUUUAUAACCUACUGAACCUGUUUUGUGAGCUGACAUGUAGCCCUCGACAGAGUCAGUUUUUGAAUGUUACAGCUACUGAAGAUUAUGUUGAUCCUGUUACAAACCAGACGAAAACAAAUGUGAAAGAGUUACAAUACUACGUCGGACAGAGUUUUGCCAAUGCAAUGUACAAUGCCUGCCGGGAUGUGGAGGCCCCCUCAAGUAAUGACAAGGCCCUGGGACUCCUGUGUGGGAAGGACGCUGACGCCUGUAAUGCCACCAACUGGAUUGAAUACAUGUUCAAUAAGGACAAUGGACAGGCACCUUUUACCAUCACUCCUGUGUUUUCAGAUUUUCCAGUCCAUGGGAUGGAGCCCAUGAACAAUGCCACCAAAGGCUGUGACGAGUCUGUGGAUGAGGUCACAGCACCAUGUAGCUGCCAAGACUGCUCUAUUGUCUGUGGCCCCAAGCCCCAGCCCCCACCUCCUCCUGCUCCCUGGACGAUCCUUGGCUUGGACGCCAUGUAUGUCAUCAUGUGGAUCACCUACAUGGCGUUUUUGCUUGUGUUUUUUGGAGCAUUUUUUGCAGUGUGGUGCUACAGAAAACGGUAUUUUGUCUCCGAGUACACUCCCAUCGAUAGCAAUAUAGCUUUUUCUGUUAAUGCAAGUGACAAAGGAACGGCUUGGCUCUUAACCUCCACCUUCCCUUCCUCUCCCGUUCUUCCAGGAGAGGCGUCCUGCUGUGACCCUGUCAGCGCAGCAUUUGAGGGCUGCUUGAGGCGGCUGUUCACACGCUGGGGGUCUUUCUGCGUCCGAAACCCUGGCUGUGUCAUUUUCUUCUCGCUGGUCUUCAUUACUGCGUGUUCGUCAGGCCUGGUGUUUGUCCGGGUCACAACCAAUCCAGUUGACCUCUGGUCAGCCCCCAGCAGCCAGGCUCGCCUGGAAAAAGAGUACUUUGACCAGCACUUUGGGCCUUUCUUCCGGACGGAGCAGCUCAUCAUCCGGGCCCCUCUCACUGACAAACACAUUUACCAGCCAUACCCUUCGGGAGCUGAUGUACCCUUUGGACCUCCGCUUGACAUACAGAUACUGCACCAGGUUCUUGACUUACAAAUAGCCAUCGAAAACAUUACUGCCUCUUAUGACAAUGAGACUGUGACACUUCAAGACAUCUGCUUGGCCCCUCUUUCACCGUAUAACACGAACUGCACCAUUUUGAGUGUGUUAAAUUACUUCCAGAACAGCCAUUCCGUGCUGGACCACAAGAAAGGGGACGACUUCUUUGUGUAUGCCGAUUACCACACGCACUUUCUGUACUGCGUACGGGCUCCUGCCUCUCUGAAUGAUACAAGUUUGCUCCAUGACCCUUGUCUGGGUACGUUUGGUGGACCAGUGUUCCCGUGGCUUGUGUUGGGAGGCUAUGAUGAUCAAAACUACAAUAACGCCACUGCCCUUGUGAUUACCUUCCCUGUCAAUAAUUACUAUAAUGAUACAGAGAAGCUCCAGAGGGCCCAGGCCUGGGAAAAAGAGUUUAUUAAUUUUGUGAAAAACUACAAGAAUCCCAAUCUGACCAUUUCCUUCACUGCUGAACGAAGUAUUGAAGAUGAACUAAAUCGUGAAAGUGACAGUGAUGUCUUCACCGUUGUAAUUAGCUAUGCCAUCAUGUUUCUAUAUAUUUCCCUAGCCUUGGGGCACAUGAAAAGCUGUCGCAGGCUUCUGGUGGAUUCGAAGGUCUCACUAGGCAUCGCGGGCAUCUUGAUCGUGCUGAGCUCGGUGGCUUGCUCCUUGGGUGUCUUCAGCUACAUUGGGUUGCCCUUGACCCUCAUUGUGAUUGAAGUCAUCCCGUUCCUGGUGCUGGCUGUUGGAGUGGACAACAUCUUCAUUCUGGUGCAGGCCUACCAGAGAGAUGAACGUCUUCAAGGGGAAACCCUGGAUCAGCAGCUGGGCAGGGUCCUAGGAGAAGUGGCUCCCAGUAUGUUCCUGUCAUCCUUUUCUGAGACUGUAGCAUUUUUCUUAGGAGCAUUGUCCGUGAUGCCAGCCGUGCACACCUUCUCUCUCUUUGCGGGAUUGGCAGUCUUCAUUGACUUUCUUCUGCAGAUUACCUGUUUCGUGAGUCUCUUGGGGUUAGACAUUAAACGUCAAGAGAAAAAUCGGCUAGACAUCUUUUGCUGUGUCAGAGGUGCUGAAGAUGGAACAAGCGUCCAGGCCUCAGAGAGCUGUUUGUUUCGCUUCUUCAAAAACUCCUAUUCUCCACUUCUGCUAAAGGACUGGAUGAGACCAAUUGUGAUAGCAAUAUUUGUGGGUGUUCUGUCAUUCAGCAUCGCAGUCCUGAACAAAGUAGAUAUUGGAUUGGAUCAGUCUCUUUCGAUGCCAGAUGACUCCUACAUGGUGGAUUAUUUCAAAUCCAUCAGUCAGUACCUGCAUGCGGGUCCGCCUGUGUACUUUGUCCUGGAGGAAGGGCACGACUACACUUCUUCCAAGGGGCAGAACAUGGUGUGCGGCGGCAUGGGCUGCAACAAUGAUUCCCUGGUGCAGCAGAUAUUUAACGCGGCGCAGCUGGACAACUAUACCCGAAUAGGCUUCGCCCCCUCGUCCUGGAUCGACGAUUAUUUCGACUGGGUGAAGCCACAGUCGUCUUGCUGUCGAGUGGACAAUAUCACUGACCAGUUCUGCAAUGCUUCAGUGGUUGACCCUGCCUGCGUUCGCUGCAGGCCUCUGACUCCGGAAGGCAAACAGAGGCCUCAGGGGGGAGACUUCAUGAGAUUCCUGCCCAUGUUCCUUUCGGAUAACCCUAACCCCAAGUGUGGCAAAGGGGGACAUGCUGCCUAUAGUUCUGCAGUUAACAUCCUCCUUGGCCAUGGCACCAGGGUCGGAGCCACGUACUUCAUGACCUACCACACCGUGCUGCAGACCUCUGCUGACUUUAUUGACGCUCUGAAGAAAGCCCGACUUAUAGCCAGUAAUGUCACCGAAACCAUGGGCAUUAACGGCAGUGCCUACCGAGUAUUUCCUUACAGUGUGUUUUAUGUCUUCUACGAACAGUACCUGACCAUCAUUGACGACACUAUCUUCAACCUCGGUGUGUCCCUGGGCGCGAUAUUUCUGGUGACCAUGGUCCUCCUGGGCUGUGAGCUCUGGUCUGCAGUCAUCAUGUGUGCCACCAUCGCCAUGGUCUUGGUCAACAUGUUUGGAGUUAUGUGGCUCUGGGGCAUCAGUCUGAACGCUGUAUCCUUGGUCAACCUGGUGAUGAGCUGUGGCAUCUCCGUGGAGUUCUGCAGCCACAUAACCAGAGCGUUCACGGUGAGCAUGAAAGGCAGCCGCGUGGAGCGCGCGGAAGAGGCACUUGCCCACAUGGGCAGCUCCGUGUUCAGUGGAAUCACACUUACAAAAUUUGGAGGGAUUGUGGUGUUGGCUUUUGCCAAAUCUCAAAUUUUCCAGAUAUUCUACUUCAGGAUGUAUUUGGCCAUGGUCUUACUGGGAGCCACUCACGGAUUAAUAUUUCUCCCUGUCUUACUCAGUUACAUAGAUGAUUUGAAGGUACCUGUACUGCAAUCUGAAACUGGUUAAGAGAACGAAUGUAUUCCAUCAGCACGGCUAUCACAAAUUUAUGAGGCAUCUCCUAGGGAGAAAAAAAUGUGGUCUUACAAAUACCAACGAGGUGCAAAAGAGGCUGCAUAUAACUCUCUAUCCAACCCCCACCUUGUUUCCAUCUUAAAAUGGCCCAGUGUUCAUCUUUCACUGGUUUUGCACACAUCGCUCCAGAACCACCCGUCAACAAUUAUGCUUUAGGCCUCAGCAUUAGAAGCCAAACUACCAGCUCUAGGGCCUCACCCAAGGAAACUCCAGUGAUUCUAAUCACUUCAAGUGACUCUAAUCACAUGAAGUCUCCUCGUUUUCAGCAACUUCCUUGUUUUGAGCAUUCUCAGUCCAGAAGAGGCGGAAAGCUGCAGCCCACCUUCUUUUCCACAAAGGCUGACAGGACAUGGGUGUACACAUCUGACUGGUCCAGCACCGCCUGGGUCCGCACCGGCCUCUUGAGGAGCGGGCUGCUUCGGCUCUGCCCUGCUUCCACCGCCUGAAAGAAAAAAACCACAAACUAUGAUCUUCGGCAUCUUAGAGGAAGGGUGCUGUUUACAGUUCAUCCACAAGGACUGAAUUCUUCGAUGUGGACCCAGGAUAUGAGCGGAAAACACUUUCUCUACUUAGAUACAACUUUUUCCUGUGCGCAUGCCUGUAAUCCCAGCUACUCAGGAGGCUGAGGCAGGAGAAUCCCUUGAACCCAGGAGGCAGAGGUUGCGGUGAGCCAAGAUCUCACCAUUGCACUCCAGCCUGGGCAAUAAGAACAAAACUCCGUCUCAAAAAAAAAAAAGCAGUUCAGAUCCGUGCAGAUUAUGCAAUAGCUGUGGGGUGUAGCCUGAGAACUUGCAUUUCCAAGAAACUCCAGAUGCUGCUCAUGUGGCUGGUCAGUGGCCCACACUGCUGAGUCAUGACGGUUUAUGGAGCCCAGCAGACCGUGUGGGACGGCACAGAAACUGCCAUUUGGGAUCAGACCUACUGAUUCCCACAGCCCAGAACACCCACAGCAAUAGAGUCCAAAAGGACUCAGCCAUCCCUCACGUCUGGCAGCGUAGGAAUGGACACUGUCCCAGCAACUGGCCCUCUUCAGUGCCUGUCUCAGACCUCUUACCCUUCCAUGAACAGCUAAAGGGGAGUGGAGUUCUGGGGCUUUUGUUGGUUUAAAACCAUUUUCAGCCUAGGACUAAUCAGAUCCUGGAAUUGAAAUAAUUCAUUCUCCUUGUCCUAAACUUUUCUUCUGGCUUCAGAAGAUAUGAUGUACAAGUAAUACAGCGGGAAUUGGUGGCGAUAAGCCAUGGUUAUUACCUUGACUACAAACACGCCUGCUAAGUGCUAACACUGAAUCGUCACUAUCUCAACAGGAUUCUUUCCCAAAAGGGAAGAAAGGUGUGGCAAAUAUAAAUAUUUCUAAUUUAAUUUUCUAAGUCCUCACUCUGGCAUAACAGAAAAAUAUACAAAAUAUUGCAAAGCA